GGUGGCGGCGCGGAGCCUUGGGCCCGGCUGCGGCCCGGCGGCGGCCCCGGCGCGGUGCGGGCGUUCGCGGCGCCCCGGGAGCUGCAGGGGCCCCGGGCGGCGGCGAGGCCGGAGAGGGGCGGGCCCGGGACACCGGCACCCGGCGCCCUCGGAGCCAAAGGCGCGCGGCGGACACGGCGGGGCCCUCGCGCGCCUGGAGACGAUGCCAAAGCUGCAGGGCUUCGAGUUCUGGAGCCGCACCCUGCGAGGGGCCCGCCACGUCGUGGCCCCCAUGGUGGACCAGAGCGAGCUGGCCUGGAGGCUGCUGAGCCGGCGCCACGGGGCACAGCUCUGCUACACGCCCAUGCUGCAUGCCCAGGUCUUUGUCCGCGACGCCAACUACCGGAAGGAGAACCUGUACUGCGAGGUGUGCCCCGAGGACCGGCCCCUCAUCGUGCAGUUCUGUGCCAAUGACCCGGAGGUGUUUGUUCAGGCGGCUCUCCUGGCUCAGGAUUACUGUGACGCCAUUGACCUGAACUUGGGCUGCCCACAGAUGAUAGCCAAGAGAGGUCACUAUGGCGCCUUUCUGCAGGACGAGUGGGACCUGCUCCAAAGAAUGAUUUUGCUGGCCCACGAGAAACUCUCUGUUCCUGUCACGUGCAAAAUCCGUGUCUUCCCGGAGAUUGACAAGACCGUGAGGUACGCCCAGAUGCUGGAGAAGGCCGGCUGCCAGUUGCUGACGGUGCACGGACGCACCAAGGAGCAGAAGGGGCCCCUGUCGGGUGCAGCGUCCUGGGAGCAUAUCAAGGCUGUGCGGAAGGCUGUGGCCAUCCCUGUGUUUGCUAACGGGAACAUCCAGUGCCUGCAGGACGUGGAGCGCUGCCUCCGGGACACGGGUGUGCAGGGCGUCAUGAGCGCAGGUGGGCAGGGCCCAGGACAGCAGCCAGGGCCCCAUGCACACGGCCUGAUACCACCGCCCAGAGGGCAACCUGCACAACCCCGCCCUGUUCGAGGGCCGGAGCCCUGCCGUGUGGGAGCUGGCCGAGGAGUAUCUGGACAUCGUGCGGGAGCACCCCUGCCCCCUGUCCUACGUCCGGGCCCACCUCUUCAAGCUGUGGCACCACACGUGCACCAGGAGCUGCGAGAGGAGCUGGCCAAGGUGAAGACCCUGGAGGGCAUCGCUGCUGUGAGCCAGGAGCUGAAGCUGCGGUGUCAGGAGGAGAUAUCCAGGCAGGAGGGAGCGAAGCCCACCGGCGACUUGCCCUUCCACUGGAUCUGCCAGCCCUACAUCCGGCCGGGGCCCAGGGAGGGGAGCAAGGAGAAGGCAGGUGCGCGCAGCAAGCGGGCCCUGGAGGAAGAGGAGGGUGGCACGGAGGUCCUGUCCAAGAACAAGCAAAAGAAGCAGCUGAGGAACCCCCACAAGACCUUCGACCCCUCUCUGAAGCCAAAAUAUGCAAAGUGUGACCAGUGUGGAAACCCAAAGGUGAGUGGGUUCCGGCUGCAAGCCACCAAGGCUUCAGCUUUGGGGGUGGGCAGGGUGGUCUCUGCACUGCUUGGGGUGGCAGGUCUGGUGCCCGCCCAGCUGGGUUUGCAACGUGGCUCAAGGUGGCAUGGAUGCCUCAGGACGGCCCCUUGCUUCCAGCCAAGCCCCUGCCCAGGCCUGGAGGGGAAGAGAGUCUGGGUGGGUGGGGGUGAGGGAGAGGCAUCUGGCUUGGGAGCAGUUCCCAGGGCUGCAUCCAGGCCGUGGGCAUCUGGCAGAGGCUUCCCCAGUGGGGCUGCUCCCCUGCUGGCCAGCCUGGCCCCGGGAGUGGUGCUGGCCACAGGCUCCCGAGAUUUCCUGUGCCCAGGGCAACAGAUGUGUGUUCAGCCUGUGCCGCGGCUGCUGCAAGAAGCGAGCCUCCAAAGAGACUGCAGACUGCCCAGGUCACGGAUUGCUUUUUAAAACCAAAUUGGAGAAGUCUCUGGCCUGGAAAGAGGCCCAGCCUGAGCUGCAGGAGCCUCAGCCAGCAGCACCUGGAACACCAGGUGGCUUCUCCGAAGUCAUGGGCAGUGCCCUGGCCUGAAGGCCCACAACCCCCACCCCCAGGACUGCUGCUGGAGCCUGGACACGUCCUACUUAAGAAAAUGCCUUUUACUCAGGGAAUCUCCUGCUACUUAAUGUGGAAAGACACGCCCAUGUCCCCCUUCGGCCCACUCUGGGGGCCUGGAAAUGCUGCAGUGGGGAGCAGGCCCCAGGCUGGACCUGCCCUGUCCUCAGCACGCGUGUGCAAAAGUGAACAAUAAAUCAUUUCAAAGAUGCGAGAGCCCACAGCCUGUGACCACUGCCCUCUCAGACCCAGGGAGGCAUGAGCCGGGGCAGGUGCGGUUGGGGCCAGUGGGGGCUUCUGAACAACAGGAUACAUCUAAAUGAAGGCAGCAUCUGGGUAGACAAAAGUGGGGGCUUAGGUCCCCUCCCCACCUCCCCUAGGCGCCUCCAUAGGCAAGUGGCCAAAGCCUCCGGGAGCUUCGUGAUGCCUCACAGCCUUGGAAGCACCGCCUGCGAGGCCACAGUGGCUGCUGCUGGGGGCUGUUGAAUCUGAGGGCCAGGCUUCUCAUUUCUCUCACCAGGCCCUGCCUCCAAGCCUAGUCCCAGGGAGACAGCCCUCAGGAACCCAAGGCCACCCAGGGGUGAC